GACCUUAGGGAAUUAGGGAGGGGCCCUCUGGCUUUAAGGGAAUGGGGACUGUAACAGAGCCCCAGCCGCAGAGCAGGGGCAACCAACAGCCGUCUCAGCCCCCAAGUCCCUGCCUCGAGGGUCUUUCUCCCUCUUCCCCGAUGUGGUUUCAGCGGGAGGCUCAGACACCUCAGCGGUGUGGUGAGGAAGGGUCCAUUGGGUCUGGGUUCGUGCUGCGGAGAUGGAGAGGACAGGCCACACCACAGCCCUAAGCUGUGGCCCAGAGGUCAGGACCUCCCUGCCCCCAGCGCCCCUGUUCUGCUGCCUCCAGGGCUCCGGGUCAGAGACUCUAUCUGCUGCUGUCCUCCGGCAAGCCCCGAUACCCGCGACCCCUUACCGCAUCUCGCCAGUCUGGAAGGCCUGGUGUGGAGACAGAAGAGCUGCCCUUGCCUUUUUUUGGGAGAACCCAGAGGGUGGGAUGGUGAUGGGGGCUGGAACAGAGUCACAUGAGACCAUAACUCCAAAAGGAGGUGGGGGCGGGGGUGGGGCUGGCUCCGUGACAUCCGUGGGGUGUAGACCUACAAGUAGGACAAGCAAGUAGGAGAGUGUUUCAGGCCCAGUGUAAGAAGACUGUUUGGGCAGAUGGGACAUUCCAAGAUGGAAUGGGCUGCCAAAGCAGUUAGGGAGCCCUCUGACCCUGGAAUAUGUGACCACUCUGGGCUACCGCCCCCAUCCCCCACCACCUCCUCCUCCAGCUUCCUGGCUGAAUGAAUAGGGGAAUCCUGGGCUGGAAUGUUUGAAAAAGCUUGUGCGGUCCAGGCACCCAUUGCUGCUUGGACCCCCUCAGCUGCUCCCUCACCUGACUCUGGGGUUGCCAGGCAGCAUAACGGGGUGCAUGGGAAGGUGAGUGCUGAAGCUGGACCACCCACUUCACCACUCUCUUCCAGCUCUGACCCUGAGAAGACCACCAGCAAAUCACUUUGCCUCCUCCCUUAUCCUUAUCAGUAUCCCUCCUCAAGAUGGGGAUAAUAAUGGCACCUCCCGUGUUAGGUGAUUAUAAAGAUUAAGUGAAAAUGAUGCCUGUGAAGCACUUGCAGGAGUUCCUGGCACAUGCUCAGCUGUCAGUAAAUAAAUAACUCUUAUUAUCCCAGCACUGUGCAUUGGGAAUACGAUUCAUUCAUUCAUUCAUUCAUUCCACAAAUAGGUGUGAAGUCCUACUUUGUACUAGACACUGUGCUAAUACUGGGGAUACAAAAAUAAAAUAGAUGAGGUCUCUGCCCUCAUGGACAGGUAAUCUACAGAGAGAAACAGACAGCGAAAAGGAAUUUAAUAGAAUUACAAAGGGGUUGGCUUAGAUCAGGGGGUCAGGAAAGGCUUCUCACAGGAAGAGGUGGGCAGGAGAGUUCAGGCAGAAGGCCUGAGGAGAAUGGGCUUAGCUGGGCACCCUUGAGGAAUGGACAGGAGGGUGUGGUGCUUUCCCUGAAAGAAGGUUCCAUUCUGUGCGGCUGAAAGGACCAGAGCAAGGGGCAAGGGUUUUAUUCUAAGUGCAGUGGGAGAGCACUGAAGGGGUUUAAGCAGCACAGGAUUCAGUGUGCAUUUAAGACGUGCACUCUGCCCAUCUAUGGAGAGGCUGAGAGUGGAUCCCAGGGAUGGUCACGAACCUCCAGAGAGCCACUUUAUAGUUUCCAAAGCUUCCACAAACACCAUCUCACCACUUGUUUUAAAUGCAGCCCGAGAAGUCAAAGGAGGUGGGGUAUGGGGGGAGCAUUUCUGUGUUCACCCUUUCUGUGACUCAGAGAAGGAUUCUAAGGUGGAGCUACAGAGCCAGGAAGUGGCAGAGGAUUUUAAUCGCCUCCUUGGAGGAGAGGAAGGAGCCUCUGAGGCCAGAAUGUAUCCCAGCCAGAAGUCAGAGGACCAUUCCCUACCCUCAGUCAUCAGAAGGGCUCCUGACCUCAGGGGCUGCUGGGGGCAGCCUGUGAGGGGCACAAGGCUGGGGCUGUGAUGACGAUGCUCCUUGGACAUGCCUGGAAGGGAUGGAGGUGGGGGCUGACUGCCCACCAGGGCCUCUGCUCCCUCACUGCUGCCUCCUCAUCCCCCAGCCUCCUCUGGGAUUGUCCUUCUCAGGGUCAGCCAGCUCCCACUGCAGUGCAGGGACCAACAUGCCCAUCUCCUCCCACAUCCUGGCCCCCACCACAGCCAACCUGGCCCCGUGCCUCAUGCCCUGCCCUCCUGACCAGCUUCCUAACUCACUGAUACUGGCUUCCACUCGGAGAGCCUACAGCUCUCUGCCAUCUACCCACCUAAGCUUGGGAAUGUCUUUCUCUGCUUGUGCUCUGUAGCCAGCUCACAUGUCACCAGGCUGAUGCACACUCAGCUCAGUGGGGCUGCAUUUACCUUUCCUAGGGAUUCCCCAGCCUGUGGUGCCCUCCCCAGUGUGGGUAGAGAAUAGGGUCUGCUGCCUCCUCUUGCAGGUAUCUCUUCUCGGAUGGGAAUGGGCGCCCCCAGCUCCCACUGGCCACCUUUAAGAGAUCAGAGGGCAACCGGGCACUGUGGCUCAUGCCUGUAAUCUCAGCACUUUGGGAGGCCAAGGUGGGAGAAGCGCUUGAGUCCAGGAGUUCGAGACCAGCUUGGAUAACAUAGCAAGACUAUCUCUAUUAAAAUAAAUAAAAUAAAAAGAUCAGAAGGCUGGCUGGGUGCUAGGCACAGAGGGCAUGGAUGUAGGCAUGGGGCUCUGGCCUGAAGGUAGCUGUCAGCCUGACAGCAUGAGGUUCCUGAUGUGCCCAUACUGGUAGUGGGUAGGGUGUGGGUAGGGUAGUGGGUAGGUUGGGGGAAGUCCUGGGGAGGUGAGGAGCACAGAGAACCCAACCCAGCCGAGUCCAAGAUGUCCAGGAUCUUGGGUCUCUCUUGACUUCACGUUUGACUAAUUUCCUCCUCCCAUCUGAGUAAUCAUAAUGAUAAAGAUAGCAGCAUUGGGCCAGGUAUGGUGGCUCACGCCUGUAAUCCCAGCACUUUGGGAGGCUGAGGCGGGCAGAUCACUUGAGGUCAGGAAUUUGAGACCAGCCUGGCCAAUAUGGUAAAGCCCAGUCUUUACUAAAAAUACAAAAAGUUGCCAGGCAUGGUGGCACAUACCUGUAAUCCCAGCUACUUGGGAGGCUGAGGCACGAGAAUCGCUUGAACCUGGGAGGCAAAGGUUGCAGUGAGCUGAGAUCACGCUACUGCACUCCAGCCUGGGCGACAGAGUGAGACUGCGUCUCAAAAAAAAAAAAAAAAAAAAAAAAAGUACCAGUACUUACUGAAUGCUGUGCCUAUGCCAAAAGCUUUGCAUUCAUUCAUUCAUUCAUUCAAAAAAUACUAAGGCCAGGCACAGUGGCUUAGGCCUGUAAUCCCAGCACUUUGGGAGGCCAAGGUUUGUGGAUCACUUGAGGUCAGGAGUUCGAGACCAGCCUGGCCAACAUGGUGAAACUCUGUCUCUACUAAAAAUACAAAAAAUUAGCCAGGCAUGGUGGUGCGAACCUGUAAUCCCGGCUACGUGGGAGGCUGAGGCACAAGAAUCGCUUGAACCCAAGAGGCAGAGGUUGGAGUGAGCCGAGAUUGCACCACUGCACUCCAGCCUGGGCAAUAGAGUGAGACUGCCUCAGAAAAACAAACACUUACUGAGUGUGUACUACAGCCAGACACUCUCCUAGGUGCUACGACUAUGUCAGUGAACAAAACAGGAAAAAAGCCCUGCCCUUGGGGAACUUACAAUCUUCUGAGGAGAAAGACAAAUUAAAAAAACAGUAUAAAUAAAUAGUAGGAUGAGAGGAAAUAUUGUGCGAUGGUGAAAAGCAGAGGAGGAGGGAGGGCUGGCACUGUAAAUCCAGUGGUCUGGGUGGCCCUACUGAGAAGAUGCCAUCUGAACAAAGAAUUGAAGGAGGCAAGGAGUGUGAGCAGUGGGGCUAUCUGGGGGAGGGUUUGCCAGGCACAGGGGAUAGUGGGUGCAAGGGUUGGAGCCAGGAGUGCCAGGGGGGAUGAGGGGACGCAGAGAAAACCACUGUGGCUGCAGGAGAGUGAGCAUGACAAAUUCCCAGAUGAGGUCAGAGAGGCCUGGGUGGAGAAGGGGGCAUCCAGACAGCUCAUGGAGCCUCUGUAGGCUCCUGUAAGGGCCUUGGUUUUUAUCCUAAGAGGGGAAGCCACUGGAGGUUUGGAGCAGGGGAGUGGUGAAAUGGGAUUUUAAGAGUUGUAACAGAAACACCAGCUGCUGUGAUGAGAACGGAAUUUAGGGGAACAAGAGUAGGAGCUGGAAGACCAGGGAAUCCAGGCAGGGAUAGUGAGGGAGGUGUUGAGAAGGGAUGGCAUUCCACAUGUAUUCUGAAGGUGGCCCCGAUGGGAUUUACUGAUGGAGUGGAUGUGGGGUGUGAGGGAAAGAGAGUCAAAGAUGACUCCUGGCUGGGCGCAGUGGCUCACAUCUGUAAUCCCAGCACUUUGGGAGGCCAGGGCAGGUGGAUCACGAGGUCAGGAGUUCAAGACCAGCCUGGCCAACUUGGUGAAACCCCAUCUCUAUUAAAAAUAAAAAAUUAGCCAGGCAUGGUGGCAUGUGCCUGUAGUCCCAGCCUCUCGGGAGGCUGAGGCAGGAGAAUCACUUGAACCCAGGAGGCAGAGGUUGCAGUGAGCCAAGAUUGCGCCACUGCACCCCAGCCUGGGCAACAGAGCAAGACUCUAUCUAAAAGAAAAAAAAAUGAUUCCUAAAAGUUUUUGGCCUGAGCAUCCUGAAGGAUGGAGAUGUCAUUAACUGAGAUGGGGAAGAUGAAGUAGGAGCAGGUUGGGGUCGAAGAGCAGGAGGUACUUUUGGGCUUGUGGCUUUGAGAGGUCUAUCGAGCUCCCAUGUGAGAUGUCAAGGAGGCUGGUAGUUAAAUGCCUGAACGUUCAAGGGAGCUAUCCAGGCCAGAGAGGUCAAUCUGAGAUUUGGGAUGGAGUUCAGAAACCCAGAGACUGAAAGUCACUUAGGAAGUGAAGGUGCUAGGACAGGAAGGGCCCCCAGAUGUGCCCUGGGAAACAAGGAAGCACCAAGAAGACCAUAAGGAGUGGCAGUGGAGAGAGGAGAAAAGCCAGAAAGGAAGGCAGAGGAAGCCACGGCCACUGGACCCUGGCGAGGGUUCCAAGGACACAGACAGUUCAGCAGGGCGACGGGGCAGCACAGGCAGAAGGCAUGGGCGCUGGCGGGGCCGUGCUGAGAGCCCAGGAGUGCCCGUGGCCAAGGUGGUACGGGCAGUAACCAGCCGGCAGAGAGCCAGCCGGCGGGUCCCACCUGCCCCACCCCCGGAAGCCCCAGGCCGCCAGAACCUGAGUGGGGCAGCAGCUGGGGAGGCGCUGGUAGGGGCAGCUGGCUUCCCACCACACGGAGAUACAGGGAGCGUGGAGGGCGCCCCCCAGCCCACGGACAAUGGCUUCACCCCCAAGUGCGAGAUCGUGGGCAAGGACGCACUGUCUGCACUGGCCCGGGCCAGCACCAAGCAGUGCCAGCAGGAGAUCGCCAAUGUGGUGUGCCUGCACCAGGCUGGGAGCCUCAUGCCCAAGGCUGUGCCCCGGCACUGUCAGCUGACUGGGAAGAUGAGCCCCGGCAUCCAGUGGGAUGAGAGCCAAGCCCAGCAGCCCAUGGAUGGCCCCCCGGUGCGAAUCGCCUACAUGCUGGUGGUUCACGGCCGCGCCAUCCGCCAGCUGAAGCGUCUCCUCAAGGCCGUUUAUCACGAGCAGCACUUCUUUUACAUCCAUGUGGACAAGCGUUCCGACUACCUGCACCGGGAGGUGGUGGAGCUGGCCCAGGGCUAUGAUAACGUGCGGGUGACGCCCUGGCGCAUGGUUACCAUCUGGGGCGGGGCCAGCCUCCUGAGGAUGUACCUGCGGAGCAUGCGGGACCUGCUAGAGGUGCCUGGCUGGGCCUGGGACUUCUUCAUCAACCUCAGUGCCACUGACUAUCCAACCAGGACCAAUGAGGAGCUGGUGGCAUUCCUAUCCAAGAACCGGGACAAGAAUUUCCUCAAGUCACAUGGCCGGGACAACUCCAGGUUCAUCAAGAAACAGGGCCUGGACCGGCUCUUCCAUGAGUGCGACUCACACAUGUGGCGCCUGGGCGAGCGGCAGAUCCCAGCAGGCAUUGUGGUGGAUGGCGGUUCUGACUGGUUCGUGCUGACACGCAGCUUUGUGGAGUAUGUGGUGUACACAGAUGACCCGCUUGUGGCCCAGCUGCGCCAGUUCUACACAUACACACUGCUCCCAGCCGAGUCCUUCUUCCACACGGUGCUGGAGAACAGCCUGGCCUGUGAGACCCUCGUGGACAACAACCUGCGGGUCACCAACUGGAACCGCAAGCUGGGCUGCAAGUGCCAGUACAAGCACAUUGUGGACUGGUGUGGCUGCUCCCCCAACGACUUCAAGCCACAGGACUUCCUCCGGCUGCAGCAAGUCUCCAGACCCACCUUCUUCGCCCGGAAGUUCGAGUCGACUGUGAACCAGGAGGUGCUGGAAAUCCUGGACUUCCACCUGUAUGGCAGCUACCCCCCCGGCACGCCAGCCCUCAAGGCCUACUGGGAGAACACCUACGACGCGGCUGAUGGCCCCAGUGGGCUCAGUGAUGUCAUGCUCACUGCUUACACAGCCUUCGCCCGCCUCAGCCUGCACCAUGCCGCCACUGCUGCACCCCCAAUGGGCACCCCACUCUGCAGGUUUGAGCCCAGGGGCUUGCCGUCCAGCGUGCACCUGUAUUUCUAUGACGACCAUUUCCAGGGCUACCUGGUGACGCAGGCGGUGCAGCCCUCAGCCCAGGGGCCGGCAGAGACGCUUGAGAUGUGGCUGAUGCCCCAAGGGUCGCUGAAGCUGUUGGGGCGCAGUGACCAGGCCAGCCGGCUCCAGAGUCUGGAGGUUGGCACUGAUUGGGACCCCAAAGAGCGUCUUUUCCGGAACUUUGGGGGGUUACUGGGGCCGCUGGACGAGCCUGUGGCCGUGCAGCGCUGGGCCCGGGGCCCCAACCUCACAGCCACAGUGGUCUGGAUCGACCCAACCUAUGUGGUGGCCACAUCUUAUGACAUCACAGUAGAUACGGAGACUGAGGUCACGCAAUACAAGCCCCCACUGAGCCGGCCCCUGCGGCCAGGGCCCUGGACUGUUCGACUCCUUCAGUUCUGGGAACCGCUGGGUGAGACCCGCUUCCUUGUGCUGCCCUUGACCUUCAACCGCAAACUACCUCUCAGGAAAGAUGAUGCCAGCUGGCUGCACGCAGGGCCACCCCACAACGAGUACAUGGAGCAGAGUUUCCAGGGCCUGAGUAGCAUCCUGAACCUGCCUCAGCCGGAGCUCGCGGAGGAGGCUGCCCAGCGGCACACACAGCUCACAGGCCCUGCGCUCGAGGCCUGGACAGACAGGGAACUGAGCAGCUUCUGGUCCGUGGCUGGACUGUGUGCCAUAGGCCCCUCUCCCUGCCCCUCCCUGGAGCCCUGCAGACUGACCAGCUGGAGCUCUCUGUCCCCCGACCCCAAAUCAGAGCUGGGGCCUGUCAAAGCAGACGGGCGACUCAGGUAGCAGGGCCCCAGCCAGUACCCGUGGAGGACCCGGGAAAUUGCACCUUACAGACAGUGGAGGGGUGUCCCCUCCCACAGGCAAGAACCAGAGGCCCAGGCUGCACACCCAUUUCAGCCAUCAAGAACCCACACAGACGGCAGGGAAGGUGGACACAGUAUGAACUACUGCUGAUGUCUCUGUUGGGGAUCAGAGGGCUGGCGGGAACGCGAGAAGGGCACCAGCAGCAUUCCACACCCAGCUCUUCCUCACCUUCCUGUCUAGUUUGAAUUUCUUUUUUUUCUUUUUUUUUUUUUUUUUUUAAUUUAAAAAGGAAAAUGGGUGGUUGGGAGAGAAACUAGAACAGAAGAUGUGCAAUAGGGCUCAGAGCAGCCCCAGGAAGUGGGCCAUGUCUGUGGGGAGCAGGGGCUUGCUGAGCCCACCUGCUAUUGUUCUGCACGAGGCUGGGCCUGCCUCACUCUCCAGGGCCUCAUGCCCCAUUCUGGGCCUGUGGUGCUCGUGGCUGAGGCUCCACAGGGCUGCAAGUGCCCUGCCAGGCUCUAAGGCCCGAAGAACAGGUGAUAUCGGGGGCGCUGCAGAGCUGGGCUCUAGCAGGACAGUUCUUUUGUAGCCAGGGGACCCUAGAAGUGGGGUGGGGCGGCUCCAGGGCUUUCCAGCAUACCCUGCCCCUGGAUGGGAAAGGCAGGGUCAGGGCCCACUGAGACCCAUGCAGAGUUUCCAGGUGUGCACUGGAAGUGAGGUCACAUGAGCAGCGUGGGAAGAAGACUCUGUCAAGACUCUCAGAAGAACCUGGAGUAAUUGUGCCUGAAGCUCAGCGUGAAGUCUGAAAUAUGCAACAGAAGAAAUAUAUCUCUAUCUCUCUACUCUGGGCUCUGUGUUUUUCCUCCUGGGUGUCAG